ACAGCCAGGCGAGAGCCGGCUUUCCGGUGCCGCCACAUUCCGGGCACCAGGCUCCGGGCUCUUCAGAGCAUUUGGGGCGGGCGACGGAGGUCCCGUCCACUCUCGCUUGGGUGCAGAAGGGCGCGGCGGUGCCAGGAAGCCGCCUUGGAGGCUCCAAGAUUAGCUCACUCAGCGCGGCCAAGCGCAGGUGCGGGGGCCCUCGCCGCCACCCUGCUUAUCUGGGGACAGUCCCGGAACCCGGUGACCCGGCUCCGCCCCAACCCGCGCCCUCGUCCACCCGCAGCAGCCAAGGCCUCUUCCCCGGCCCCGGGAGCCCGCGCCACGCCCGUCGCUCGCGCGUUCCAGUCCAGGCUACAGCAGGUAUCGCGAUCCCGGCCCUCGGCCCCGCGCUCCCCUCCCCCGCCCCUGGCGCUCUCCGAGUGUGGCCGACCAUGAGGAUUCCCAGUCUUGCAAAUCGUGGGAGCGUGUCAACCGCCCCGUUUCUUUCCAAAGCCGGGCAUGGCCCGGAAGCAGCUGAUCAGAUCUUAGUUCUGAAUGUAUAGUUCGGGUACGAGAAUGUGACCCGUGAAAGUUCAGAGGAGUUAAGUAAUUACAGCGUUCUGAAAGCGAACGUUAAAGGGAAUUUACAACCGAAAAAAGAUGCCGGUCUUCUUCCCCCAUCCCAGCUUGCAAUUCACAGAAGCACACAUUAGGGUGGAGCCAGAAGGAAUUACGGAAAGGACAAUGAGGACAUUGAGAGGGAGGGUAUGGGGGGUUAAAGUUAGUCCUCCGAGGCCAAGAAGCAGAGUGUCUUGGCCUAGUGUCUGAAAAUCGCAGCGCAGGACGGAACUUCCGAGAGCCUAUACCUCCCCACUUCCCCCUCCAGUUUACAGAUGGGCAAACCGCUGUCCCGGGUGUCUGUCAGGUCUAGUAGCCCAGAAUCUCAGUGCCUAGGCUUCACUGUAAAUAAUAAACUAUGUAAAUAACAUUUACAAAUAUCCUUUGUGAGCUCAGAAACUCAGCAUUACCAGUAACUGGGUAGUGGAACGCAUCCAUCUUCGUCGUUUACUCCUUCUCCAGGGGCUCUCCAGCCUGCAUUCCAUGGCCAACAGCAGUGCAGCUGCAGAAGCACUUCUGGAAGCCUCCUGACUUGAACUAGACCUUGGACACCCUCUCCAGAGCCCAGCAAUUGUGAGGGACUGAUGGAGAAGUAUGUGGCUGCUAUGGUGCUGAGUGCAGCUGGAGAUGCCCUGGGGUACUACAAUGGGAAGUGGGAGUUCCUCCAGGAUGGGGAGAAGAUACACCGGCAGUUGGCCCAGCUGGGCGGCUUGGAUGCCCUAGACGUGGGAAGGUGGAGAGUUAGUGACGACACAGUGAUGCACUUGGCCACAGCAGAAGCUCUUGUGGAAGCUGGGAAAGCCCCUAAGUUGACUCAACUGUAUUACCUCCUUGCUAAGCAUUACCAAGACUGCAUGGAAGACAUGGAUGGGCGGGCACCAGGUGGUGCCUCGGUGCACAACGCCAUGCAGCUGAAGCCGGGCAAGCCCAAUGGCUGGAGGAUUCCCUUCAACAGCCAUGAGGGCGGCUGUGGGGCUGCCAUGCGGGCCAUGUGCAUCGGUCUCAGGUUCCCACACCAUAGCCAACUGGACACACUGAUCCAAGUGAGCAUCGAGAGUGGUCGGAUGACCCACCACCACCCAACAGGCUACCUGGGGGCCCUUGCGUCUGCUCUUUUUACAGCCUAUGCUGUGAAUAGCAGACCACCCUUGCAGUGGGGAAAAGGACUGAUGGAGCUGCUACCAGAAGCUAAAAAGUACAUUGUCCAAUCAGGCUACUUUGUAGAGGAAAAUCUUCAACACUGGUCCUACUUCCAAACCAAAUGGGAAAAUUACCUAAAACUUAGAGGGAUUUUGGAUGGAGAAUCAGCCCCUACCUUCCCUGAGUCUUUCGGUGUGAAGGAGAGGGAUCAGUUCUACACCUCCCUGAGCUACUCUGGCUGGGGUGGCAGCAGUGGGCACGAUGCCCCCAUGAUUGCCUACGAUGCUGUUCUUGCUGCAGGAGACUCCUGGAAGGAGCUUGCCCACCGAGCCUUUUUCCAUGGUGGAGACAGUGAUUCUACAGCUGCCAUUGCUGGCUGCUGGUGGGGAGUUAUGUAUGGUUUUAAAGGAGUGAGUCCCUCCAACUAUGAGAAACUAGAAUACAGAAACCGGCUGGAAGAGACAGCUAGGGCUUUAUAUUCUCUCGGGUCAAAAGAAGACACUGUAAUUUCCCUUUAGGGAGACGUGAUGUUCACUUCUGAUGGAUUCUUCUUUUGUGUAUUUCCUUUUCUGCUAUUUCUUUUCAGUUUUUCCAAAGUCAAGAGUCUUAACCUUGUACUCAGGGAAUUUUGAGAUAACAAGUCCCUUGGGCACCUUAAGCUCAGUUUUUUCAGGCUCAUCCUGUUCUUCCAGAAUCUAUCCCUUUUCUUACACUGAAGAGUCCUUUAGCUCAAUUGAUAGGGUCAGCGUCUCGCAAGCAAAAAAUCUCAUGACCUCAUAUUUGAGUCUUCAUUUUCAUCAUCUACUUGUUCUAAAAGUUUUUUCUGUUUGUCUCAAGUUGGGUUCCCACAAAGUGGACUUUGAGACAAAGAUCUGAAUGCAAGCAGUUUAUAUGGGAGAUGAUUCCAGGAAAUACCGAUAUGAGAAUGGGGAAAUGAAACCAGGAAGGGAAGAGAGCUAGUAUGGGGUAUGUUAAUGAGCAGGUUUCCACUGUGGGCGGUUGGCACUCUGCCAUCUGAGUCCUCUGCCUAAAGCAUUCCUCAGAACUGUCCCAUUUGAAGGGCAAGCAAACCUGGGGUAUUUAUCCACUGACUUCCAUCUGACACUGGUUGAGGACCACUGCCAGGGAUGCUAACUCCCUGGUAAUUCUUGGCUUACCCUUUGUACAAACCAAACCUUAGUGUCUUCAGGUAAAGACUCAGAGAUACUUGCAGGGGCAAGCUGUAAAGGGCAUGGGAACAGUGAGGGACAUAUGUGGGGUCCUAACAAUAUCUGCUAGGCUGGUCUACCUCCUAAAUAUACUCUGAAUCUAUCACCUCUAUUGCCUUCUUGCACUGAGGAUUUUUCAGCUGGAUUUCUGCAAUCCAAGCUACUCAAGUCUGGGAGAUGCUGCUCUGAGCUGCUCUCAGUACUCUCCUCAUCAUGGCAGUUAACACAUUACCAAUUUUGUUAUUGUCUGUUUGCUUGUUUGCAUUAUUUCUAAACAGAACCUAGCACAGUGCUUGGGCAGCCAAUAGGCAUUAAUCAGUAUCUAUUGAGUGUUAUGAACUAGCCUCCUAGCUCGUGCUUCCCUCAUUACCCUCCAGAGUUAUGUUUACGAAUAACAAAUUGACCAUGCUAAACUAAUCAUGUUCCAAUGAAUACAUCACCUUUCUUCAUUUCUUGAUGCUCUUCCCAAUCCUUGUCUACCUGAUAAUAAAUUCUUACUUGUCCUUCAAGACCCAACUCAGAUAGAUAGAGCUUCCUGAGUGAAACCUGCUUUGAUUGUUCAGGCACUUGGCCACCUUCUCCUCACUCCUCCCACAGCCUUCUGUCUUGGCCUUGUCAUCACAUCAAUCCUGUUGUGUGGUGCUGUGUGUCUUCUGGGUCAGUCCUAGGCACAUGCUGCCCAGCACAUGUCCACCUGGGAAAUGAGAUGCCAUCGUCACAUUCAUUUGGUCACCCUCAGUCCAGCCAGUGGGCUUGCUCUCAUUUGGCCUGUUCUCAGGGGUGGGAAGGAAGAGCGUCCCUUCCUUCUCCUUUUGAGAAAACCACAGAACUAUGACUCUCAUGAUUUUUCCUUUGUGAAAUCCCUGGUUUUCAGCUGGAAGCGGUGGGUAAAUGAGGUCUGAUGAUAGCAGUCCUGCCACCUUCUAGUUCAUCCCAUAGGAAUGUUUUUCCAAGUCCUUCCAGUCUUUUUAGAACGUGGUGGAGGAGGGUUGUGUGUGCCCCAGGGGGUCGGGGGUAGGGGAUGCAGGGAGGAUCUUAGCAUUUGUUGUUUUCUAGUGCAGGGCUUUAGCCACAAUUGUAAACAACAGGAAAAGGCUCUUUAGAGAUCCUAUUAGAUUUGCUUUGCCGAUUGUCACUCUUCAUCACAGGCACAUUUCAAAAAGAGGUUAGACUUUCAGACUUCUUUUUUCUCAAACCUCAAAACUUCCACCCCAAACUUCGCUCUCAGCUGGUGACUUUGCUUCUUUAUGUGUGUGUAUGUGUGUCAGAGAAAGAGAGAGAGAGAGAGAGAAGGGAGGAUGAGAACGAAUGGGGGGAAGAGAUAAACUUUAUGCAUAACAUUAGGGUAAAUCAAUAAAGAUGGUCUGACACAUCGUA